AGACUUCUGCUGGCAGUUACUGAGAGAGAUAGGCUUUCCAUCCAUGGCAGCCAUUUACUUUUGCUCUGGGAGACGUUUGUAAUAGAAAAGGCACAACUGGGGUAUUUAUUCAUUCCCCCCGUUCCUCUAGUGUUUGGUGGCGUUGCCGUUGCAAGUGCGCAGGGCUAAAAUGGACUGGUUAUCUUAGGAUCAUGGAAAACCUGGAAUCAAGGCUCAAGAAUGCCCCCUAUUUUCGUUGUGAGAAGGGAACCGAUUCCAUCCCUCUAUGCCGGAAGUGUGAGACGUGUGUCUUAGCCUGGAAGAUCUUCUCUACCAAAGAGUGGUUCUGCAGGAUCAAUGACAUAUCACAGAGGAGGUUUCUAGUUGGCAUUCUGAAGCAGUUAAAUAGCUUAUAUUUGUUACACUAUUUCCAAAAUAUCCUUCAGACCACACAGGGAAAGGAUUUCAUCUAUAACAGGUCCCGGAUCAACCUCAGCAAGAAAGAGGGGAAAGUUGUGAAGUCCUCCUUGAACCAAAUGUUGGAUAAAACAGUAGAACAGAAGAUGAAAGAGAUCUUGUACUGGUUUGCGAACAGCACCCAGUGGACCAAGGCGAAUUAUACUCUCUUACUGCUGCAGAUGUGCAACCCCAAAUUACUGCUCACUGCUGCCAAUGUGAUCAGAGUCCUGUUUCUGAGAGAGGAGAACAAUAUCUCAGGUAAACAAGGCCACAGGCAGAGACUAGAGGGCCCCCGAAGACCAGAAGGCAAGGCUUCAGAAAUCUGGCUCAAUCAAGACAUCACAGAUGUGUGUUUUUCCCCUGAGAAAGACCACAGCUCCAAGUCUGCGACCUCACAAGUCUAUUGGACAGCCAAAACUCAGCACACAUCCCUUCCUUUGUCCAAAGCCCCAGAAAAUGAACACUUGCUUGGGGCAGCAUCUAACCCUGAGGAACCAUGGAGGAAUUCACUCCGGUGUAUAUCCGAAAUGAAUAGGCUGUUUUCUGGAAAAGGAGACAUAACCAAGCCAGGGUACGAUCCCUGCAAUCUAUUGGUUGACCUGGAUGACAUCAGAGACCUGUCUUCUGGGUUCAGCAAAUACCGAGACUUCAUCCGUUACCUGCCCAUCCACCUCUCCAAGUACAUUCUAAGUAUGCUGGGGUGUAUGAGGGGAUUUCCCAGACACCUCCCCUCUUGGCCCAGUUCUGGGGUUUCUGGGUCCAUCUUUUUUUUUCCAGGAAUGCUGGAUAGACACACCCUGAACAAGUGCGCCUCUGUGAGCCAGCACUGGGCCGCCAUGGCUCAACAGGUCAAGAUGGACUUGUCAGCGCACGGCUUCAUUCAGAACCAGAUUACCUUCUUGCAGGGGUCCUACACAAGAGGAAUUGAUCCUAAUUAUGCCAAUAAGGUUUCUAUCCCAGUUCCUAAAAUGGUAGAUGACGGGAAGAGCAUGCGUGUGAAACAUCCGAAGUGGAAGCUGAGAACGAAGAAUGAGUACAACCUGUGGACUGCAUACCAGAACGAGGAAACGCAGCAGGUCCUGAUAGAGGAGAGAAAUGUUUUCUGUGGGACCUACAAUGUUCGCAUUCUCUCUGACACGUGGGAUCAAAACCGAGUCAUCCACUAUUCCGGGGGAGAUCUGAUAGCUGUGUCAUCUAAUCGAAAGAUCCAUCUUCUGGACAUCAUACAAGUGAAAGCGAUACCCGUUGAAUUCCGAGGCCAUGCUGGGAGUGUCCGGGCCCUCUUCCUGUGUGAGGAGGAAAACUUUCUCCUAAGCGGGAGCUAUGACCUAAGUAUCAGAUACUGGGAUCUGAAAAGUGGGGUUUGCACACGAAUCUUCGGUGGUCACCAGGGGACUAUCACUUGCAUGGACUUGUGUAAGAACAGGCUCGUAUCUGGAGGAAGAGAUUGCCAGGUAAAAGUAUGGGAUGUAGACACAGGGAAGUGCCUGAAGACGUUUAGACACAAAGACCCCAUCUUGGCCACCAGGAUCAAUGAUACCUACAUUGUGAGCAGCUGUGAGCGAGGGCUGGUGAAAGUGUGGCACAUUGCCAUGGCCCAGUUGGUAAAGACUCUCAGUGGCCAUGAGGGAGCCGUGAAAUGCCUGUUCUUUGACCAGUGGCAUCUCCUCUCAGGAAGUACUGAUGGCCUGGUCAUGGCCUGGAGCAUGGUGGGGAAGUACGAGCGCUGCCUGAUGGCCUUCAAGCAUCCCAAGGAGGUGCUCGACGUGUCCCUUCUCUUCCUCCGGGUCAUCAGCGCCUGUGCAGAUGGCAAGAUCCGAAUUUACAAUUUCCUCAACGGGAACUGUAUGAAGGUGUUAAAAGCCAAUGGCAGAGGUGAUCCUGUGCUGUCCUUCUUUAUUCAGGGCAACAGGAUGGUGGUCAACACAGAGAGCAAUGUUCUCAUGUUCCAGUUUGAGCACAUAAAGUGGCAGUAUGCCGUGGAAAAAACGAAACAAAAGAAGAAUAAGGAGAAAGAGGAGGAAAAAGAAGAAAAUAGUCUCAUGGAAAUUCUCUCUAAGUGUAAUAUUCAGGUUCACAGCCCAAGAGAGUCUGUAUCCAGUAAACAAACUGUGAUCCAAGAGCUCCUACCAGGCAAACCUCCCAAGUCCCGAGUACUCCUGAAGCCGGCCAAGUUCUCUUCAGCAGUGUUAAUAGAGGAACUUCAAAGUCAAGGAAAGUCAAAAUCACCCCGAAGAGAUGCAGGCCACUACCUUUGCUUGUCUUUGAGAAACUGGAAUGAAUACAAUGCCUGGCUUCUCCCAAGAGUGACUGGUUUUCCUUAAUUGUCCCUUUUCUGACUUGAGGCCACAGAGGGAGAACCUUUCUAAGCAGAUGAUGUGGAGAAAGCACAAAAACAAGGACAAUUGGAAACUCCUGGAAAACUGCCCAGUCACCCAAAGAAAAAGUCUUGGAAAAUCCCUAUGUCACCUGACCAAUUCCUCCUGACUGUUAGCGCCCUGCAGCACGCCCAUAAUUCCGGGGAAUUUGCCUAUCCCUGUAGGCCCCAAACAGAAAUUACUGAUGUCUGGGGACCUUCAAUUUCAUACCCAAGGAAGGUCUUGAAUUUCAAAGGAAAAUCAAUCCAACGUGCAGUUGAUCGGUUGAGAUUGAGCAAUCCUCCUAUAGAUGUGAAACGAACCAGUAUUCCCCUUGAAAUCCAGAAACUGCAGCCCAACUUGAAGAUCUCUUUGCACAGUCCUAGAGUCCAGUCCACCAUACCCCAGCCCAUGAUUAUCCGCUCCAGGUUCUCUGGCAGCUUAAAGGGUGGAGACCAAGUGACCAGUUCAAUUGAAAGGGCUGUGUGCAGUACGGGUCCCCUGACCAGUAUGCAGGUCAUUAAACCAAACCGCAUGCUAGCUCCACAAGUGGGCACAGCCACCCUGUCUCUUAAGAAAGAACGGCCUCGCAUCUAUACAGCCCUUGAUCCUUUUAGAGUGAACACUGAGUUCGUGCUGUUGACCGUGAAGGAGGAGAAGGAGCACCAGGAAGCCAAGAUGAAGGAAUAUCAGGCCAGGGAGUCCACUGGAGUGGUUGAUCCAGGAAAAGUCAGCAAAGCUGCAUGGAUCAGGAAGAUCAAAGGCCUGCCUAUUGAUAAUUUCACGAAGCAAGGGAAAACAGCGGCCCCUGAACUUGGACAAAAUGUAUUUAUCUAAACCAGCCUUGGGAAAUUACAAUGUUUUACAAUAAACAGAAAGCCAAGCGGA